AAAUUCUCCUGGCGGCCUCCGUUCAGACGCGGCAGCUGUGACCCACCUGCCUCCUCCGCAGAGCAAUGGCGGUGUCUGCCGGGUCCGCGCGGACCUCGCCCAGCUCAGAUAAAGUACAGAAAGACAAGGCUGAACUGAUCUCAGGGCCCAGGCAGGACAGCCGAAUAGGGAAACUCUUGGGUUUUGAGUGGACAGAUUUGUCCAGUUGGCGGAGGCUGGUGACCCUGCUGAAUCGACCAACGGACCCUGCAAGCUUAGCUGUCUUUCGUUUUCUUUUUGGGUUCUUGAUGGUGCUAGACAUUCCCCAGGAGCGGGGGCUCAGCUCUCUGGACCGGAAAUACCUUGAUGGGCUGGAUGUGUGCCGCUUCCCCUUGCUGGAUGCCCUACGCCCACUGCCACUUGACUGGAUGUAUCUUGUCUACACCAUCAUGUUUCUGGGGGCACUGGGCAUGAUGCUGGGCCUGUGCUACCGGAUAAGCUGUGUGUUAUUCCUGCUGCCAUACUGGUAUGUGUUUCUCCUGGACAAGACAUCAUGGAACAACCACUCCUAUCUGUAUGGGUUGUUGGCCUUUCAGCUAACAUUCAUGGAUGCAAACCACUACUGGUCUGUGGACGGUCUGCUGAAUGCCCAUAGGAGGAAUGCCCACGUGCCCCUUUGGAACUAUGCAGUGCUCCGUGGCCAGAUCUUCAUUGUGUACUUCAUUGCGGGUGUGAAAAAGCUGGAUGCAGACUGGGUUGAAGGCUAUUCCAUGGAAUAUUUGUCCCGGCACUGGCUCUUCAGUCCCUUCAAACUGCUGUUGUCUGAGGAGCUGACUAGCCUGCUGGUCGUGCACUGGGGUGGGCUGCUGCUUGACCUCUCAGCUGGUUUCCUGCUCUUUUUUGAUGUCUCAAGAUCCAUUGGCCUGUUCUUUGUGUCCUACUUCCACUGCAUGAAUUCCCAGCUUUUCAGCAUUGGUAUGUUCUCCUACGUCAUGCUGGCCAGCAGCCCUCUCUUCUGCUCCCCUGAGUGGCCUCGGAAGCUGGUGUCCUACUGCCCCCGAAGGUUGCAACAACUGUUGCCCCUCAAGGCAGCCCCUCAGCCCAGUGUUUCCUGUGUGUAUAAGAGGAGCCGGGGCAAAAGUGGCCAGAAGCCAGGGCUGCGCCAUCAGCUGGGAGCUGCCUUCACCCUGCUCUACCUCCUGGAGCAGCUAUUCCUGCCCUAUUCUCAUUUUCUCACCCAGGGCUAUAACAACUGGACAAAUGGGCUGUAUGGCUAUUCCUGGGACAUGAUGGUGCACUCCCGCUCCCACCAGCACGUGAAGAUCACCUACCGUGAUGGCCGCACUGGCGAACUGGGCUACCUUAACCCUGGGGUAUUUACACAGAGUCGGCGAUGGAAGGAUCAUGCAGACAUGCUGAAGCAAUAUGCCACUUGCCUGAGCCGCCUGCUUCCCAAGUAUAAUGUCACUGAGCCCCAGAUCUACUUUGAUAUUUGGGUCUCCAUCAAUGACCGCUUCCAGCAGAGGAUUUUUGACCCUCGUGUGGACAUCGUGCAGGCCGCUUGGUCACCCUUUCAGCGCACAUCCUGGGUGCAACCACUCUUGAUGGACCUGUCUCCCUGGAGGGCCAAGUUACAGGAAAUCAAGAGCAGCCUAGACAACCACACUGAGGUGGUCUUCAUUGCAGAUUUCCCUGGACUGCACUUGGAGAAUUUUGUGAGUGAAGACCUGGGCAACACUAGCAUCCAGCUGCUGCAGGGGGAAGUGACUGUGGAGCUUGUGGCAGAACAGAAGAACCAGACUCUUCGAGAGGGAGAAAAAAUGCAGUUGCCUGCUGGUGAGUACCAUAAGGUGUAUACGACAUCACCUAGCCCUUCUUGCUACAUGUACGUCUAUGUCAACACUACAGAGCUUGCACUGGAGCAAGACCUGGCAUAUCUGCAAGAAUUAAAGGAAAAGGUGGAGAAUGGAAGUGAAACAGGGCCUCUACCCCCAGAGCUGCAGCCUCUGUUGGAAGGGGAAGUAAAAGGGGGCCCUGAGCCAACACCUCUGGUUCAGACCUUUCUUAGACGCCAACAAAGGCUCCAGGAGAUUGAACGCCGGCGAAAUACUCCUUUCCAUGAGCGAUUCUUCCGCUUCUUGUUGCGAAAGCUCUAUGUCUUUCGCCGCAGCUUCCUGAUGACUUGUAUCUCACUUCGAAAUCUGAUAUUAGGCCGUCCUUCCCUGGAGCAGCUGGCCCAGGAGGUGACUUAUGCAAACUUGAGACCCUUUGAGGCAGUUGGAGAACUGAAUCCCUCAAACACGGAUUCUUCACAUUCUAAUCCUCCUGAGUCAAAUCCUGAUCCUGUCCACUCAGAGUUCUGAAGGGGGCCAGAUGUUGGGUGCAGAUGUAGAAGCAGCCAGUCACAGACCCAUUCUAUGCAAUGGACAUUUAUUUGAAAAAAAUUCUCAAAAGUUUUUUUUUUUUUUUUGGGGGGGCGGGGUUCUAAAGCUGUUUUUAACUCCGAGAUUACAACUUAGAGGAACCAAGGAAAUAAAGCAAAUAAGAUUUAACAACCCAAGAUUAAGAGGCCAGGAAGAGGUUAGACGCAAUGUGAAACUGUCCUCCUAGGAUAAGGUUUAAAGUGGCUUUUUGGGGGCUGGGUGCCGUGGCUCACGCCUGUAAUCCCAGCAUUUUGGGAGGCUGAGGUGGGCAGAUCACUUGAGGCCAGGAGUUCGAGACCAGCCUGGCCAACAUGGCAAAACCCCUUCUCUACUAAAAAUACAAAAAUUAGCCAGACGUGGUGGUGGGUGCCUGUAAUCCAACUACCCAGGAGGCUGAGGCAUGAGAAUCGCUUGGGCCCAGGAGGUGGAGGUUGCAGUGAGCCGAGAUCGAGCCACUGCACUCCUGGGCAACAGAGCAAGACUUCGUCUCAAAAUAAAUAAAUAAAGUGGCUCUUGGGGAAAAGCAAUUUAAUGUACCACGAUGAAUAGCUAACUGUUCCCAAGUGUUUGCUAUGUGCAACACACCGCGUGAGCAGUGUUACCUGCAUUAUUACAUUAGGCUGAGAGGUAAAAUAAUUUGCCCGAAGACAUACAGCUAGUGACGAAUGGACUGAUGGUUUGAACUUAACGUCUAUUUGACUUAAGGUCCUGCACCCUGCCACUUGUAAUUUUCAGAAUCACUGAUAAUCUGAAAUAAUGCAGCUUAAAACAUGUUUUCUUAAUUAAAAGUAUAAUUGGAUGGUGGUCAGGUUGUAAAUGCACACAAAGUAAUUUAUCUUCAUUGCAAUUUUGGUUCCUUCUUUGUUCCUAUUAUCUAUAUACACCCAGUGUUUCACUAGCAGUUAUGAGAGCAGUCAGAAUAGCAGCAUCAAAGUUAAAUAAGGAAAUCUAGAUGAUUGCUAGAUUUUCUCUAAAAAUAAGCUUAGUAUUUGGUAUUAUUCUAGCCUUUGGUGAGCAGAAGGGGAGGUAAAGUAAGAAUUAACUAAAUUUAGUAAGGGAUUAGGGAAUGCUUAGACAUUUUGUAGGUUGGGGUAUACAAGGGUAACUCAGGAAGCUCCUCAGUUCAGUGAAAAUUCAAAGGGUUGGCACUGAGCUAGGAAGCGAGAAUGCAGGGUUAUGAAAAAGGAUCCCUGCUUUGGGAGCUCAUGGACUUGUAGCAGAGACCGGUAGUAAAUUGGCAGUCUCAGUAACUUCUGUAAAUGAUUGCAUCUCUUUGCAGGCUUCUCUUCCCAUACUCUCCCCCACUCCUCCUUGGACAGUGUUCCGGGGGUUCUUUCCUAAGCAACUGCUUUUUCAGUAUACAUACUUCAGAUGAUUGUGUCUACUCCAGGAUUUCCAACGAUGCUAGGUUUCUUUCCUGUGCCCUAGACGUAUAGGUCUAAGUUCCACCUGGAUAUCCCACAGGGCUAUCAAGCUCAGUUCAUCCUAAACAGAACUUACAUUCAUCCCCAACUCAGACUUCCUUAUUCUUUAUUAUUGAAUGGCAGCUCUGUACCUUAGCCAAGCUGUUAUCUCUAGGUCAUCAGCCUUGACUCUUCCUUUUUCCUUGCAUUUCUUAAAAUUGCCAAGUCCCAUCAAUUUUACCUCCUGGAUACCUCUUGAAUCUAUUUUUUUUUAAAGACAGGGUUUCACUCUAUCACCCAGGCUGGAGUUCAGUGGCACAAUCUUGGCUUACUGCAGCCACCACCUCCUGGGUUUAAACGAUUCUUCCACUUCAGCCUCCCAUGUAGCUGGGACUACAGGUGCCCACCACCACGCCCAACUAAUUUUUGUAUUUUUAGUAGAGACAUGGUUUCCCACAUUGGCCAGGCUGGUCUCAAACUCAUGACCUUAAGUAUCCACCUGCCUUGGCCUCCCAAAGGGCUGGGAUUACAGGUGUGAGCCACCGUGCCCAGCCAAAUCUGUUUUCAUUACUACCUAUAUCUGUAUUUUCAACCUUUGUAUUAGCAUCUAGUUAGGGAUAGACCAGGACAGGGCCGACAUGUUAGUUGUCAAGCAGAUUGCCACCCUCCCCCACCACUGAGGAGGCCAAAUGGAGUUUGGUGGAAAAUCUCUAAUUCAUUCAAGGUAUUAUAUGGGCAAGCAAUGGCUGUGGCACAGGGUCCCCUGAUUACUUUGUAAGAAUGGGUGGGAGGGAUGCUGAUUUUCAAUCCUUUUGCAGAUCUUCUCUCAUAGUAACACAAUAGAAGAUACUUUGCCACUAUGUUGUUUGCCAAACUCACUGUACCUACUUGACUGGUAACAAAAGUCCCAAGAGUUACUUGGGAGAAGACACUUGAAAAAGUAUUUUUCUAAAUAUGGGCAAGGAUGCUGCCCUUCCCCAAACUGUUAGUAUACCACCUCUCUGACCAAUUUUCCCAAGGAAGAUAUUGGGGUAGGGUGAGGUGUAAAGAAAAAGUGGUCAUGUAAAUACUGGUAAUAAAAGCUGUUCAGUGGGGUAGAGUUGGGUUGCAACUGUAGCCAUUCUAAAAAUGGGCUAUCAAUGUCCUUUUAGCCAAAAGACUUUAGUAUACAUCCUCCUCAUUCUACCCUCAGGAUUUGGAUCUUUGCCCCUGAUGGGUAUCCAUCCCCUUUGAAACUUUAGAAAGGCAGGUUAUAUACAGAAUGUUCAACCUAAAGACAUUUCCUUAAGUCAUACUUUCAUGCUUUCUAAACUAUAAUCACCCUUAUCAUCCCCUGCUGUUAUGCUUUCCCUCUGCUCCCUGUGGCCUAAUGUUCCUCCACCACCUUAUUAACCUUCAGGAUACUUUUCCCCUAGGCUGGGCAGGACAACACUAUCCCCUUGGUCCACAAGCUCCCUCAAGGUUGGGGAAUCUUUGUUUACUUAGCAAAUACUGAACAUAACCUUAAAGCGGUUACUUUUGAAAACUUCUCAUGCUAUUCUACCAACUUGGAGGCACCUAUCCAUGCUCAUUCCCCUAAUGUAGCCAAUAUGGUUAUCUGCAAUGUAUUGGCAUCUAAAAACUCCCUUAUGAAACUGCCAGACUUGUUCUGGAACAUUUCAAUUACAUGCAAAAUUCAGGUUCUCAAGUUGGAACAAGUCUAAUUGACACACCUGCAUAGGUUUUAACCUUGCCCUCCCCCUACUUCCCAACAGAUUUCCAAGUUUUUUGAGAAGGAACCUUGCUCUGGCCCAGGCUGGAGUGCAAUGGCGCCAUCUCGGCUCACUGCAACCUCUGCCUCCUGGGUUCAAGUGAUUCUCCAGCCUCCUGAGUAGCUGGGAUUACAAGCACCUGCCACCACACCCAGCUUUUUUGUAUUUUUGGUAGAGACGGGGUUUCAGUUUGCCAGGCUGGUAUCAAACCGUGACCUCAGGUGAUCCACCCGCAUUAGCCUCCCAAAGUGCUGGGAUUACAGGUGUAAGCUACCAUACCCAGAUUUCCACGGCUUUUUUUUUAAGUCUCACUCUGUUACCCUGGCCGGAGUGUGGUGGCACGAUUUCAGCUCACUGCAAGCUCCACCUCCCGGGUUCACGCCAUUCUCCUGCCUCGGCCUCCUGAGUAGCUGGGACUACAGGUGCCUGGCUAACUUUUUUAUAUUUUUAGUAGAGACAGGGUUUCACUGUGUUAGCCAGGAUGGUCUCGUGAUCUGCAUGCCUUGGCCUCCCAAAGUGCUAGGAUUAUAGGCUCACGCCUAUAUUACUAUAUAGUGGCCUAUAUUACAGGCCACUCCGCCUGGCCUCCAAAUUUCCAAGUUUUUAAGUCUCCAUGCAAACAGGCAUAAGCAAGCACUCCUUGGCUCUACAUUUGCAGGACAAGCUGGACCACCAUUCAGAUGUUGGUAGAAAUGUAAUCCAAGUGGCUAUUCUCUAUGCAUGUAGCUCCUAGGUUCAAGAGCAGUGUGGUCUGCGGAUUUUCUACACAACCUGCCAUAAAUGAAAUUUAAGCCUUUGGAAAUUUAUAGCAUUUUCAGCUAAUUUGCAUUAUUUAUCUCUGCAAGAUAUUGACUAGAAAUCACGUUUCAGAACUUCUCAGAUGAAAACAUCAUACAACCCUUAAAACUAAGCUCAUAAUUUAAAAAUGUAUGCAGAUUAAUAGGCUUAAAUUGCCAGGACUUUAGAUAGACAUUACCACUUCCAGGUUAAUACUUUUAGCGGUUUUUAUGCCUUCAAUGGUUUGAAGCCCUCAACCUUAGUUGAAAACUUAAAAAUGGCAUUGAAUGGCUGCUGCAAUAAGGACACAUGAAUUUUGGCUUAAGUGGACUAGGAGGACUAAAUCUUGCUUAGGCUUUUAAAAAAUGCCCACCCACUGGGUCUAGGGAUUGAGGUUAUUUUCCUGAAUUAUGGCUAAUUAUGGAUUACAAUUCAAGGUUAAAGAUACACAUAUAGUAUUCUCAGGUUAUUCAUAUGAUAGCAUUUUUUAAGAGCCAAAGUCUCAGUCACCCAGGCUGGAGUGCAGUGGCUUGAUAAUGGUUCGCUACAGCCUCCAACUUCUAUGUUAAAGUGAUCCUCCUACCUCAGCCUUUCAAAGUGUUGGGAUUAUAGGCACGUACCUAUGGCCCCAAAGCACUUUAACAAAUGAGUAACAGACACAGUUAAGGUAGAACCUAGCAUUUUAUUUAGAUCUUCAUUAAACUGUUGGAAUUGAGAACCAGACAUACGUAAUAAACCUCCAAAAAUAGAUCCUGAAAGGCACUUUCUGCUUAGGGCAAGCAGUCAUGGAAUAAGCAUGUAAACAAGCUGGCUUCUCUGUACCACACCAGCCAAGUCAGCUUUCUCCAUGGCCAGCCGCACCAGCUCUGCCCUCCCUUCUGUUAACACCAGCCAGACCCCCUGUAGGUCUAACCCAAGGUUUUUCUGUAGGACACCUUGGCCUACCUGGGAAUGCUGGAAACAUGUUGUUAAAGGAAUCAUGGUGUUGAGAGAAAAAAAAAAAAUCUUUUAAAAGCUGCCAUCUGAGGUGAUGGCUUCUCUGUACUUACGCCAUACCCCAGAAUACAAUAAAUAAGCAAUUAGAAAACGUUCAAGUAUGAAGGGAUUUCCUCCUCCCCGCCAAAAGCACUGCUCUCUGAAGGAAGCUGGUUUCUCUGUAGCUACACCAGCUGUUCAGAAAGCUCAUUGGACCUGGUUUUGAAAAUAAAACAAAGUUAAAACCC